GGCCCGCGGCGCGCUCUGGCGUGAAGGGCCGGUACGUGAGGGGGAGGCCUGGCCCGCGGACCCGGCUCCCAGCUCGGGCAGUUCUUACAGCCCAGCUCUGUGCUCUGCUCUCUGCUGGCUCCAGGAGGGGUCCUCACUCGCUGACCACACUGACCUCAGGACCAAGGGAACAAAACACAGCAGGGGCAAUCCAUCCGGUCCACGGAGAAGUGCUAAACCCCAAAGGGUAAAUGAGAUUCCCACAGGAGGAGCAGGGAGGAGACAACAGGCAGGGUGGAGGGAACAGCAUGAGGAACAGCAUUUGAGCCCAGCGUGUGUGGCCUCCAUGUGCUGAAUGCGUACUGGAUACCAAGCUUGCUCUACGGAGGCCCUGUGAAGGUGGCUGUGGAUCACAGAUAUCCUCAGCUCUCUCCAGAGCUCAACACAGUACCAGAUGCUCCAGAAAUGUUUGCUGAACUGAAUUUGACUGGAAAGGAAAACAGAGCCCCAGGCCUGCGCGGUGGCUCACGUCUAUAAUCCCAGCACUGUGGGAGGCCGAGGCAGACGGAUCACUUGAGGUCAGGAGUUCAAGACCAGCCUGGCCAACAUGGUCCCAGCUGCAGGGCAGCCAUGAGCCUGGUGGCCUGUGAGUGCCUGCCCAGCCCCGGCCUGGAGCCUGAGCCUUGCUCACGAGCACGGUCCCAAGCUCACGUGUACCUGGAGCAGAUUCGCAACAGGGUGGCUCUGGGAGUGCCUGACAUGACAAAACGUGACUAUCUGGUGGAUGCGGCCACGCAGAUCCGGCUGGCCCUGGAGCGCGAUGUUAGUGAGGACUAUGAGGCGGCCUUCAACCACUAUCAGAAUGGCGUGGACGUGCUGCUCCGUGGCAUACACGUUGACCCCAACAAGGAGCGACGUGAGGCUGUGAAGCUGAAAAUUACCAAAUACCUGCGGCGGGCAGAGGAGAUCUUCAACUGCCACCUGCAGCGGCCGCUGAGCAGUGGAGCCAGCCCCAGCGCGAGAGAUCUCGCUGUGUUGCCCAGGCUGGUCUCGAACUCCUUGCCUCAGGUGCAGCUGGUCCAGGACCCGGCAACCGGAGGGACCUUUGUGGUGAAGAGCCUACCCAGGUGCCACAUGGUGAGCAGGGAGCGGCUGACCAUCAUCCCACACGGAGUCCCCUACAUGACGAAGCUGCUCAGGUACUUUGUGAGCGAGGACUCCAUCUUCCUGCACCUGGAGCAUGUGCAAGGAGGCACUCUCUGGUCCCACCUGCUCUCCCAGGCGCACUCCCGACAUUCUGGGCUCAGCUCUGGCUCUACCCAGGAGAGGAUGAAGGCUCAGCUCAACCCCCACCUCAACCUCCUGACCCCAGCGAGGCUUCCCUCAGGCCAUGCCCCUGGCCAGGACAGAAUCGCCCUGGAGCCUCCUAGGACUUCUCCGAACCUUCUCCUAGCUGGGGAGGCCCCAUCCACCAGACCCCAGAGGGAGGCUGAAGGUGAACCCACAGCCAGGACCAGCACCUCUGGCUCCUCGGACCUUCCAAAGGCCCCAGGUGGCCACCUGCACCUUCAAGCUAGGAGGGCUGGCCAGAACUCAGACGCUGGGCCCCCUCGGGGGCUCACUUGGGUUCCUGAGGGGGCCGGCCCGGUGCUAGGGGGCUGUGGCCGAGGCAUGGAUCAGAGCUGCCUGUCAGCAGAUGGGGCCGGCCGGGGCUGUGGCAGGGCCACCUGGAGUGUGAGAGAGGAGCAGGUGAAGCAGUGGGCGGCAGAGAUGCUGGUAGCGCUGGAGGCGCUGCACGAGCAGGGGGUGCUGUGCCGGGACCUCCACCCCGGGAACCUGCUCCUGGACCAGGCAGGUCACAUCCGGCUCACAUAUUUUGGCCAGUGGUCAGAGGUGGAGCCCCAGUGCUGCGGGGAGGCCGUGGACAAUCUCUACAGCGCCCCAGAGGUGGGUGGGAUUUCCGAGCUGACGGAAGCCUGUGACUGGUGGAGCUUUGGGUCUCUACUGUAUGAACUGCUGACGGGAAUGGCACUGUCCCAGAGCCACCCUUCAGGAAUCCAGGCCCACACCCAGCUCCAGCUGCCCGAGUGGCUCAGUCGCCCAGCGGCCUCUCUGCUGACUGAGGUGAGGUGUAGCCCGGCCAGAGGAAGCAGCUGCCUAGCCUGAGGAAGGUGCUGGGAGGGGCACAGAACUGUGUCUGAACCACGUGUGCUUCGUGCUCAGUGUCUGAUGUGGGUGCAGAGGGCAGUAGGGGCAACACAUUUCUAUAUGUUGGUGGCCAACCACCACCAAUGUUCCCAGGGUAAAAUGGGGGUUCUGUGGGCCAGGCUGCCAGGGAGCAGGCCCCCUAGAGGCCAUAGUGGUUGGAGUCCCUGGAGGUCACCCCAUGCCUCCACAGCUGGAGUGGCCCAGCUGACUGGGCCUCUCUCUGCAGCUGCUGCAGUUCGAGCCUACCCGGCGCCUGGGCAUGGGAGAAGGUGGUGUCAGCAAACUCAAGUCCCAUCCCUUUUUCAGUACCAUCCAAUGGAGCAAGCUGGUGGGGUAAGAGGGCAGAGCGGGUGACGGAAGCAGCUGGCCUGGUCUGGAUCGCCUCUCCUCCUUGCCUGACACCCAACCCAGGGCUGGCCCUCUAUCAGCGGGCUUUGGGCGAGGAAUGGAGGGCACUGUCUGUCCUGCUGGGCUCCCACUGGGGCCUCAGAAUUAUGGCCACCACCCAGGAAGGGCCAGCUCCUGGAAAAGCUGGAGGUGGGGGCAGUCAAGGCUUGCCCUGCUAAGCAGCUUGAACCAUCUACCCAUCAGUCAACAGACCCGUUGAGCAUGUGGACUCACCAUGUUAAAGGUUGCCUUCUGUGGCACUGGCGCUGAGCUGUUGACCACCUGCUGCACCCUACUGUGAGGUUCUGUGACUCACUCACUGCCAUGUUGUGCCCCACUCAGGACAUCUCUGGAGACUCAUCUCAGGACACUGAUCCACUGGCUCAGUGGACCCAAACCAGACUGUCCUGGCUAGUCCUCUUAGUCACACAGCGAGUAGGCCUCUUCCACCAGAAGCUGUUCGUGCAGCUGGGGAGGCCCAGAAGCAGGGAUGCCAUCUGUUGUGCAGGGAGGGAUGAGGUAGGGGACAGGAUGACCCCCACCCCCACCCCCCCACCCCCGAUUCCUGACCAUGCCCCCUAUCUUGUGAUUUCAGACUUGGGAGAGCAAAAGGGAGGGGAAGAAAAUAAGAGUAAUGGGGGGAGGAAGGAAUGCAUGGGUCUGCCCCUUAGAGCAAGUCUGAAACCAGAAUCAAGAGUCCUCCUCCCCAGUGGGCCUGUGUGGGGGAAGAGGGGCAGCCUGCCCCAGGGGUGCAAGAGGACAGCAAUUCAGCUUCCAGGCCAAAGCAGUUUAGACAAGGUGUGCCCAUCAGGACUCCCUCUCAGGCCCUGGCUGUUUACCAUGUCACUGCCUACUGUGACUUCAUGCCCUUUUGGGAUAAGAAACCACAAAACGCAUGGAACAACUAUCCAUGGCUCUUAGCCAGAAAUGUCUUGCCUCUGGUCUCUGAAAAGCUGGGGUGAGUGGUUACCUCAAAGACAAUUGCCUCCAGUUUGGGGGCUCCUCUCAGGGUUCACCCUGUCACCGGGGCGUGGGACCGACCUGGGAAAUUUCCACUAGAGUUUUGCCCUCAGCUCCUCCCUGCCAGCAUCCCAGUCACCACCAGGUGGCGCUUCUGACACGGUCCACGUGCCUGGCUCUGAAGGCCCAACUGUCAGACCAGACCCCUCACUCAUGGUGGGGAGACUUGACUUCCUCGGGCUCUUCAGGAGACUGAGACAGAGAAGACAAGUGAAAGCGCAGCCUGUACAUGACUCUCUGUGGUCCACGUCCUGCCUCUCCCUGGGGUUUACACGGCCCCAAUAAAGCCUGCUCUGGCCUACGGUGUUCUCGCUUCUUCCAUGCAAUGACCACGGCUCAUUGGGGCAGGUUGGAAGGCUCCCCUGUAGAAGCUCCAGAGUGAAGUCAAGAGCGAGCUUGGGGCUGCCAGGAAGUAGGACGCAGGGCUGGUGGUGAGCAGCAUGCCAUGUGGGCCUCAGGGGAAGGGGUGGGGUCGGGGAGGACCAGGUUCUGUGGGGAAGAGGAUGAAGAAGCCUUGGAAGAGGCUCAUGGUGCCUGGGGGAAUACCAGUUUCAUCCUCACAGUGACCCCUUGCAACAGACGGUAGCUCCUGAGAAAACUGAAGCUCAAAAAGGUUAAGGACACAACCUAGCCAGAGUUGCAAGUUAGUGUUCCUUCUGCUACUCUCCCUAAGUCAGGCUGGACCACUUCCAACCACCGCUUCAUGAAGCACAAGUCCCUUCUGGAACUUCUGUGCUUCAUCCACCCAAAGCUACACAUCUGACACUUUGUUGGGCCCUGAGUUUAGAAUACUGUGGGUCCCAGCUCUUACAGUCGACCUCCUUUCGAUAAAAUGGGGUAAAUAAUGCCUAUUUUGCAGGUUUACCAGAUAGAUAAAUUAAAGCUUCUAACACCAAAUCCUGUUCUUCCUUUCAUUCAACCUAAUUUGUUUUUCUAUCUACUAGAGCUCUAGUUCUACUCUCUGGGACCCACUUCCCUCCUGUGACAGACCUUCACAGAGGGAUGGCCUCACUGCAAGAGCUCAGCAGACAGGGACUCUGGAAAAGACAAGGCUGUGUUUAAGCCUGGACUCCAUCACACCUGCCACCUGCAGUCUAGGUUAGCUACCCACCCUGUACACUCACGCUCACUGACCACUGCUCCUAGGUCAUCAACCCUCACCUGUUCAUGUGUAUUGACCUUGAGCAUCUUGGUCCACAAGGCUAUCAAAUCCAAAUGAAAUGAGAUGCCCCCACUCCUCCCAAAUCCAUCACUGAAAUAAUGUAAGCCCACACAAAAAAUGCAAGUCUACUGGUGUUUUGAAAGGGCUUCACAAAGAUGGUGACCCCAAAUUCUCUAUUCUAGAGUAUGGCUUGACAGGCUCAAGGAAGGUGGGGCACUAAGAGACUAUGAUGCUUUAUGGAAACAAAACAAAAAACAUCCUAAGCCCCCCAACCAUCUGUAUGGACCCCUCGUCUCAGUCAAGGGUAUUCCAAAGUUAACCUGAAACGCUAGUUCGGGCCAUGGUGGGAAGAGGGAGCCAGCCAUUCCUCAUUAUACUCCCCUCCCUUUUGGAAUUACUGUUAAAACAGGCUCCUUAAGUCUGAUGAGAAGCAUUUACAAUCUAUUUUCUCUGAAGCCUGCUGGCUGGAGGCUUCAUCUGCAUAAAACCUUGGUCUCCACAACCCCUUACUGUAACCCAGACAUUCCUUUCUAUUGAUUCCAGGUCUUUAGAUAAUAACUCUUUCAACCAAUUGCCAAUCAGAAAAUCUUUGAUUCUGCCUAUGACAACAUCCCCAGGUCUUGAGCUGUCCUGCCUCUCCAGACCAAACCACUGUACAUCUUACAUGUACUGACUGGUAUCUUAUGUCUCCCUAAAAUGUAUUAAAUGUAUAAAACUAAGUUGUAGCCAGACGACCCUGGACACAUGUUCUCAGGAUCUCCUAAGAGUUGUAUCACAGGCCAUCAGUCACUCACACUUGGCUCAGAAUAAAUCUCUUCAAAUAUUUUUACA